GACUCAGAGCGCUCCGGGCUGCAGGAGAGGAAGCCCAGCCUGUUCUACCAGAGAACUUGCCCAGGUCAGAGGUCUGCGUAGAAGCCCUUUUCUGAGCAUCCUCUCCUCUCCUCACACCUGCCACUGUCCUCUGCGUUGCUGUCGAAUUGUUCCAACUUCCUAACUCCAACAUUAACCCUUUGAAUGUAUUCUUAUGCCAGAGAAAGGCACAUAAAGUACUGGUGUUUGAACAGAUAACUUCCAACAUGUCCUCUGUUUGUGAUAUGUCUUUUCUGCAGAAAUCUUGCAUCACCAUGGUGCACUUCUGUGGCCUACUCACCCUCCACCGGGAGCCAGUGCCGCUGAAGAGUAUCUCUGUGAGCGUGAACAUUUACGAGUUUGUGGCUGGUGUGUCUGCAACUUUGAACUACGAGAAUGAGGAGAAAGUUCCUUUGGAGGCCUUCUUUGUGUUCCCCAUGGAUGAAGACUCUGCUGUUUACAGCUUUGAGGCCUUGGUGGAUGGGAAGAAAAUUGUAGCAGAAUUACAAGACAAGAUGAAGGCCCGCACCAACUAUGAGAAAGCCAUCUCCCAGGGCCACCAGGCCUUCUUAUUGGAGGGGGACAGCAGCUCCAGGGAUGUCUUCUCUUGCAAUGUGGGUAACCUCCAACCUGGGUCGAAGGCGGCAGUCACCCUGAAGUAUGUGCAGGAGCUGCCUCUGGAAGCAGAUGGGGCUCUGCGCUUUGUGCUCCCAGCUGUCCUGAAUCCUAGAUACCAGUUCUCUGGGUCGUCUAAGGACAGUUGCCUUAAUGUGAAGACUCCUAUAGUCCCUGUGGAGGACCUGCCCUACACACUCAGCAUGGUCGCCACCAUAGAUUCCCAGCAUGGCAUUGAGAAGGUCCAAUCCAACUGCCCCUUGAGUCCUACCGAGUACCUAGGAGAGGACAAGACUUCUGCUCAGGUUUCCCUGGCUGCUGGACACAAGUUUGAUCGGGACGUGGAACUCCUGAUUUACUACAAUGAGGUGCAUACCCCCAGCGUGGUUUUGGAGAUGGGGAUGCCUAACAUGAAGCCAGGUCAUUUGAUGGGAGAUCCAUCUGCAAUGGUGAGUUUCUAUCCAAAUAUCCCAGAAGAUCAACCAUCAAAUACCUGUGGAGAGUUUAUCUUUCUCAUGGACCGCUCGGGAAGUAUGCAGAGCCCCAUGAGUAGCCAGGAUACAUCUCAGCUGCGAAUACAGGCAGCCAAGGAAACACUGAUUUUGCUGCUGAAGAGUUUACCUAUAGGCUGUUAUUUCAACAUCUAUGGAUUUGGCUCUUCCUAUGAGGCAUGCUUUCCGGAGAGUGUGAAGUACACUCAGCAAACAAUGGAGGAGGCUCUGGGGAGAGUGAAGCUUAUGCAGGCCGACCUAGGGGGCACUGAAAUCUUGGCACCACUCCAGAACAUUUACAGGGGACCCUCCAUCCCAGGCCACCCCCUACAGCUUUUUGUCUUUACAGAUGGAGAAGUUACAGACACGUUUAGUGUAAUUAAAGAAGUUAGGAUCAACAGACAGAAACACAGGUGUUUCUCAUUUGGUAUUGGAGAAGGCACCUCCACCAGCCUAAUAAAAGGUAUUGCCCGGGCAUCAGGGGGCACCUCAGAAUUUAUCACAGGCAAAGACAGGAUGCAGUCCAAGGCUCUCAGGACUCUGAAACGCUCUCUGCAGCCUGUGGUAGAGGAUGUCUCUCUGAGCUGGCAUUUGCCUCCUGGUCUGUCUGCUAAAAUGCUUUCCCCAGAACAGACUGUCAUCUUUAGGGGUCAGAGAUUAAUCAGCUAUGCCCAGCUGACCGGGAGGAUGCCAGCAGCAGAGACAACAGGAGAAGUAUGCCUCAAAUAUACACUCCAGGGCAAGACUUUUGAGGAUAAGGUGACAUUUCCUCUACAACCCAAGCCUGAUGUCAACCUCACCAUUCACCGCCUUGCUGCCAAGUCCUUGCUCCAGACCAAGGACAUGGGCCUCAGGGAGACUCCAGCAAGUGAUAAAAAAGAUGCAUUGAACCUUAGCCUUGAGUCUGGUGUCAUAAGCUCCUUCACAGCUUUCAUUGCUAUCAAUAAGGAGCUCAACAAGCCGGUUCAGGGGCCUCUGGCUCAUAGGGACGUCCCAAGGCCAAUUCUGUUGGGUGCUUCUGCCCCAUUGAAGAUAAAAUGCCAAUCAGGUUUUCGAAAGGCCUUACACUCUGACCGUCCUCCUUCUGCAUCUCAGCCCAGAGGGGAACUUAUGUGUUAUAAGGCCAAGACAUUCCAGAUGGACGAUUACAGUCUCUGUGGGUUGAUAAGUCACAAGGACCAGCACAGUCCAGGCUUUGGAGAGAAUCACCUUGUGCAGCUGAUUUACCACCAAAAUGCAAAUGGUUCCUGGGAUCUGAAUGAAGAUCUAGCCAAGAUCCUAGGUAUGAGUUUGGAAGAAAUAAUGGCUGCACAGCCUGCCGAGCUUGUGGAUUCCUCAGGCUGGGCCACCAUCCUGGCCGUGAUCUGGCUGCACAGCAAUGGUAAGGACUUGAAGUGUGAAUGGGAGCUUCUGGAAAGGAAGGCCGUGGCCUGGAUGCGUGCCCAUGCAGGCUCCACCAUGCCUUCGGUUGUGAAAGCUGCUAUUACUUUCCUGAAGUCAUCUGUGGAUCCUGCUAUCUUUGCCUUUUGAAGAUACCAUCCAGAAAAAGAAGUGCCUUUAAUUUGCUACUGUCAUUUCCUCUAGUAUCACUUUUGCUGUGAUGAUGUGUUCUUGUGUAUUAUAACUCUUUAUUUUUUGCCAUAAAAGUAAAGGAUGCUUACUCCACUUCGCUUCUCUGCUCCAGGUUCACUUUGGAUAUGAUCUUUCUUUUCCCAACAUAUGCCCUCAGAAAAGUGACAGUGGUCCCAGAACCUAUUCCCUUUCUUGAGGGAGUUCAAAACAUUCAUAGGCAGUAAUGUUCCUCCCAGGGUUUCCAGGGAAACAACAUGAAAAACAGGUGACAUGAACUACAGACUAAAGAUUGCAGCAUUUAUGUUAGAGAAUGCUUGAAUUAGAGAAUUUUCUGCAUUAUCUUUGUCUGUUCACUUUCUAUCUUAUAUACUUAUCAGGGCCAUACUGGUAAGCUUGCGUAGGAGGAGUUAGAGGGAAGUUGAAAGCCAACAUCUGGAUCAAUGUAAUGUCAAGAUCACAAAGACAGAGACUGCAGGGGUCCACUGUGAGAGGUGACACUGUUGGGGACCUUCCUGAUUCAUUCUUCUUGGGCUUUGCUAGCCUGUACAACCUACAUGUCUUUUCUUCCACUGCCUGAAAGACUUGGGUUGAACUAUAACUGUUGGAGAGAGAUGUUCCUCUUUAAUCAUGAAACACCUUAAGAAGUCUAUAAUGCAAUCCUUAGUCCUACCCUGAACCUAUGUGUCCUCUAAGUCAGGCCCUGAUCUAGUGCAGUAAAGGGAAGGGUGGGCUUAAUGGGAGCUUUGCCUGGGACCUGAACCUGGAGCACUUACCGCAUUAGGAAGAAAGGAGCUCCCCGUAAUCGUUCCUGACCCUUGUGUCUCAUAUACCCUAUCCUGGUGGAAAUGACCCUAUUUGAUAUGCUGUCCCUUAAAAUAACUUGUAUCAAUAUUAAAAUGACUAUUUCUACCCUUUGAUGAGUAAAUGCAGUGGUUCUUAAAGUGGUCUCGUCUCCCUACCCCACAAUAUUUUGGUACUGCCACUUUGGGAAGCCAAACUAGGAUAGUAAAUUGACCGGAACACAGUUGUGGAAAUUUGACCUGAAGUUAGUGAAAUAAAACUUAGUAGGGAAAAAAAGCUUAGCAAGAGGUCUACUCCUCCAUAGAUUCAUUUAUUGAACUUACAUUGGUUUUAUUGUCCCUUGUUUUCUGUUCCAGCUUUUCUGAUGCCUCCACUGUUCCCAUGGUAUCCUGACCCUCUAUCUUCUGUUGUAGGCUGACUUCUUUUAUAUGAAGCAAGUAAAGGAUACUAAUAAGAAUACCACUGUAGAAUCCUGACCAUACCCUUAAAUAGUUAUGUGAUGAUGGGCAAAUGAUUUCACCCUCAGGCACUUAAUAUCCUCAUCUGUAAAACUAAGGGAUUAAACUAGAACUUUAUUAACACUUUCGAGUUCCACUCAGAAUUCCUAGAGGAACAUCGGUGACUUUUCACUCAGAAAGUGGGUGGACUAGGCCUGAGUUUCUUUAAGUUGUUGAGUUACCUGGUAUUAGGAAGACUUGUGUGACUUGCAUAGUGGACUCUAAUCUCUCAGUCUUUCUUCCAAGUUUGUUUAUGCUGAAUGUGAUCUGCGGAACAGGGUUGUUAGAAAUGCAGCUUUUUAGAAAUGCAGAAUUUUAAUCGAUACCAGGAACUACUUUAUUUAACAAGGCUCCCAGGUAUCAUGCAUGCACAUUGAAGUUUGAAAAGUAAAGGCUUAAUAUUUUCAUGAAAUAGGCUUAUAUCCAAGCCUGCCAU